GUUUACAGUUCGGCACGUAGGACGGAGGGUAGUGCGUCUAGAGACACAUAUUCCCCACGGAUUUGACGAUGGUGUUCGGUCUUGAAUGGAAAUGUAGUCUUAGGCCAGUCUUAGGUUUUUGAACAGGAUAGUAGGUAUCCGGAGUCGAUUGAGGGCCAGAGCAGGCACUGGGGUUCGGAUCCUGGGCAAAGUUUCCCACGUUGAGGGUCUCGAGGACGCCUAGAUCUCUUUCCCAGGGCCAUGGCGAACCCGAAGCUGCUGGGAAUGGGGCUAAGCGAGGCGGAGGCGAUCGGUGCUGAUUCGGCGCGAUUUGAGGAGCUGCUGCUGCAGGCCUCGAAGGAGCUCCAGCAAGCCCAGACAACCAGACCAGAAUCGACACAAAUCCAGCCUCAGCCUGGUUUCUGCAUAAAGACCAACUCCUCGGAAGGGAAGGUUUUCAUCAACAUCUGCCACUCCCCCUCUAUCCCUCCUCCCGCCGACGUGACCGAGGAGGAGCUGCUUCAGAUGCUAGAGGAGGACCAAGCUGGGUUUCGCAUCCCCAUGAGUCUGGGAGAGCCUCAUGCAGAACUGGAUGCAAAAGGCCAGGGAUGUACCGCCUACGACGUAGCUGUCAACAGCGACUUCUACCGGAGGAUGCAGAACAGCGAUUUCUUGCGGGAGCUCGUGAUCACCAUCGCCAGGGAGGGCCUUGAGGACAAAUACAACUUGCAGCUGAAUCCGGAAUGGCGCAUGAUGAAGAACCGGCCAUUCAUGGGCUCCAUCUCGCAGCAGAACAUCCGCUCGGAGCAGCGUCCUCGGAUCCAGGAGCUGGGGGACCUGUACACGCCCGCCCCCGGGAGAGCUGAGUCAGGGCCUGAAAAGCCUCACCUGAACCUGUGGCUGGAAGCCCCCGACCUCCUCUUGGCCGAAGUUGACCUCCCCAAACUGGAUGGAGCCCUGGGGCUGUCGCUGGAGAUCGGGGAGAACCGCCUGGUGAUGGGGGGCCCCCAGCAGCUGUAUCAUCUAGACGCUUAUAUCCCGCUGCAGAUCAACUCUCAUGAGAGCAAGGCAGCCUUCCACCGGAAGAGAAAGCAAUUAAUGGUGGCCAUGCCGCUUCUGCCGGUGCCUUCUUGAUCAGGGUGUCUCCUUGUGCUUCUGAGAUGUGGAGAAGAGGCUGCUGGCUUCCCUAAAAGUUGAAAUAAAAGAUUUUUGCCUUUG